GGUCCGCAAAGCCGGUGGCGCCCGGAGGCUGCACGGAGAGCGGUGCCCGCGUCAGAGCCUCGCCCUGUCACCAGGCUGGAGUACAGUGGCGCGAUCUCGGCUCACUGCAACUUCCACCUGCUGGGUUCAAGCAAUUCUUCUGACCUCAGUGACCGAAGGAAGAGACCAAGAUGAAUGCAGAGCCCGAGAGGAAGUUUGGCGUGGUGGUGGUUGGUGUUGGCCGAGCCGGCUCCGUGCGGAUGAGGGACUUGCGGAAUCCACACCCUUCCUCAGCGUUCCUGAACCUGAUUGGCUUCGUGUCGAGAAGGGAGCUCGGGAGCAUUGAUGGAGUCCAGCAGAUUUCUUUGGAGGAUGCUCUUUCCAGCCAAGAGGUGGAGGUCGCCUAUAUCUGCAGUGAGAGCUCCAGCCAUGAGGACUACAUCAGGCAGUUCCUUAAUGCUGGCAAGCACGUCCUUGUGGAAUACCCCAUGACACUGUCAUUGGCGGCCGCUCAGGAACUGUGGGAGCUGGCUGAGCAGAAAGGAAAAGUCUUGCACGAGGAGCAUGUUGAACUCUUGAUGGAGGAAUUCGCUUUCCUGAAAAAAGAAGUGGUGGGGAAAGACCUGCUGAAAGGGUCGCUCCUCUUCACAGCUGGCCCGUUGGAAGAAGAGCGGUUUGGCUUCCCUGCAUUCAGCGGCAUCUCUCGCCUGACCUGGCUGGUCUCCCUCUUUGGGGAGCUUUCUCUUGUGUCUGCCACUUUGGAAGAGCGAAAGGAAGAUCAGUAUAUGAAAAUGACAGUGUGUCUGGAGACAGAGAAGAAAAGUCCACUGUCAUGGAUUGAAGAAAAAGGACCUGGUCUAAAACGAAACAGAUAUUUAAGCUUCCAUUUCAAGUCUGGGUCCUUGGAGAAUGUGCCAAAUGUAGGAGUGAAUAAGAACAUAUUUCUGAAAGAUCAAAAUAUAUUUGUCCAGAAACUCUUGGGCCAGUUCUCUGAGAAGGAACUGGCUGCUGAAAAGAAACGCAUCCUGCACUGCCUGGGGCUUGCAGAAGAAAUCCAGAAAUAUUGCUGUUCAAGGAAGUAAGAGGAGGAGGUGAUGUAGCACUUCCAAGAUGGCACCAGCAUUUGGUUCUUCUCAAGAGUUGACCAUUAUCUCUAUUCUUAAAAUUAAACAUGUUGGGGAAACAAGAA